GCCUGUGCCCCGUCUCUAUGGCGGCCCCAACGGCCGUCCAGGACGUGGAGCGAAAUGAGCUCGGGCGCUGACGGCGGCGGUGGCGCUGCGGUGGCGGCGCGGUCGGACAAGGGCAGUCCCGGGGAGGACGGUUUCGUCCCGUCGGCGCUGGGGACCCGCGAGCAUUGGGAUGCUGUCUAUGAGAGAGAACUGCAAACUUUCCGAGAAUAUGGAGAUACAGGUGAAAUCUGGUUUGGAGAAGAGAGUAUGAAUCGACUAAUAAGGUGGAUGCAGAAACACAAGAUUCCACUGGAUGCUUCAGUGCUUGAUAUUGGAACUGGAAAUGGUGUUUUCCUGGUUGAACUUGCAAAAUUUGGUUUCUCUAAUAUUACUGGAAUUGAUUACUCUCCUUCUGCAAUUCAGCUUUCUGGAAGUAUUAUAGAAAAAGAAGGUUUAUCUAACAUUAAGUUAAAGGUAGAAGACUUUUUGAAUCUCUCCACACAGCUGUCUGGAUUUCAUAUUUGUAUUGACAAAGGGACUUUUGAUGCCAUAAGCCUUAAUCCUGACAAUGCAAUUGAGAAGAGGAAGCAAUAUGUGAAAUCUCUCUCCAGGGUGUUGAAAGUAAAAGGCUUUUUUCUAAUAACGUCAUGUAAUUGGACCAAGGAAGAGUUGCUAAAUGAAUUCAGUGAAGGAUUUGAACUUCUCGAAGAGCUACCAACACCCAAGUUCAGCUUUGGAGGCAGAUCUGGAAACAGUGUAGCAGCAUUGGUUUUCCAAAAAAUGUGAGACUUUUUCUUGGACGAAUUCAGGUAGCUACACAGAAUCUACACAGCAAAGUUAACCUGACACAGAAAAUCCUUGUGCAAAUAAAUGCUUAGUAAGUACACAGGAUGCACAUGUUGAAUAGAGUAUACUGGAUUGGUGAAAGAAAAUAAUAAUAAUGAGCAUCUAAGUGGUUGGGUUUUAGAGAUCAAUCAAGAAUAAUUUUAAUUUUCUUUUGUAUUUGAAAUGUAAAUAGUUUUCUUUUCGAUUAAAAAAAUUUCCUAUAACUGCUAAACAGUUAAAAACUUUAAAGUAGUAAAUGAGUUUAUAGAAAGCAUGUAUUCUUGAUUUUUGUGCCUUGGUAAAGUUGAUAACUAUUUAUGAAUAUUUGACCAAAUUAUUCCAGCAUCAGAAUAAUAAGCAAAAUAACUUUGUUAGUGUUUUGUUAGACUGUUUAUGAAAUAUAACAAGAAAUACUAUUUUGUGUUGGAUGGCGGUUAUUUUUAAACUUAAUUAAUACCUGUGAAAAGGCCUCUUACCUUUAUGUAUAUAAUUAAACAAAAUCAGAGAAAUGUAUCAGUUGCUCAAGUUAUCAAGCCUGCAUUUUGCAGCUAUGGUCUUCUACACACUGUAAGGGUAGUAGAAGGAAAGAGAACUAAGGAAUGUUAUUAUUUGCUAGCGCUAUGUUAAGUUGUCUUAUUAAGUAAUUGAGUCCUUUCAAUGUCUUCUUGAGGUAUGUAUUGCUUGUUCUUGUUUCUACGUAUAAGGAAAAUGAAGCUGAGAGAAGUGAAGUCACUUUUAUGAGGUUCAACAGUACAGGAUGGAGCCAGGAUUUUUAUCUGGGUCUGUCUGACUUUAAAACACAUACUCUUCUCCUAGCAUAUUCUGCCUCACAGGUGCUUAGUCUUUGCCUUUGUAGCAUUUACAGUACAGCUGGAGACCCAUGAUGAUUACAUAUAAAGUUCAGUUAGAAAAGAUGGGUAGUUACUUUAUUAGUGUUCAUCUGUGGAGUAUCAGAAUAGCAGUCAGCCAACUCUGUCUCAUAUCAUCCUUCAUUACUUUUCCCCAUCUCCCUACUCAAAGACUUGCCUCUAUUAAGAAUUUUGUCAUUCUUCUGUGAAAGGGUAGUGUAAGUUAUAUAAGCCCUCAGCGAUACAUGCACAAAGAUGUUCUAGUUAGGGGCUAAUUUGGCAAGAGAAACAGUUUAUUAAUGUUUUUGAAAAGAUAAGUCAUAUUCAUACUUAAUACCAUUUUGUAUUUGUGGUAAUAUUUUAAUAUUGGAGCUAAAUACAAAUUUUUGCAUAAUUUUUUGAUGAUUUUCAGCUUUGUGGGCCUAUUGGGUUACAUAAGUGACUUUUUGUUUGGCAAAUGUUACUCCUGUAUUGAGUAAGUCUAACAUUACGUCCCUUUUCUUUUUGGGGAGGGGUAGCCAGAGGAGUGAGUUUUUCAUUUAGAUCAACAUUGAUCAACCAUUAAGACAAGAUAGUUGAAGACAUGUAUGUGGACUGUCAACAAAAAUAACAUUUUUUGAAAAGCUUUUAUUUUCAACAUGUAAAAAGUGAGAAAUUACUUCAAAAUAUAUGCAAUUUAAAUUUUUUAGAAGAUUGUGUUGAUUUUACCAAGACAGGAGAUCUUAAACUGUAGAAACUUUUAUAGUUUUUGAGAUCGGGUCUUUGUUUUUUUUCACAUUAAUAUUCUUUGAUUUCAAAUAUAACAUAGAUAAGUACUCUUAGAAUUUUGAGUUAAGUAUAUGCUAUUUUAAUGUGCUAAUCCUACAAACUAGGCUUUCUGUGUGACUAGACUGAGAUGUUGAGUUUGAUUCACAAAAAGCUUAGAAUGGUUCUUUGUUGAAAAGCUUUUCGAGUCACUAUUUGGGGCAUGUUAGUGCCAUUUGCAAAGGUGAAGGUUUUCUUUUUUUUUUUUUUUUUAACCAUAGAGCUUUUGAUAAGGUUAGGAAAAGGAAGUUGUCAUCUCUUCUUAUUACUCUAAUCCUGCUGGAAGCUAGCUUCUUAGGGACUAAAACCAGAACAAAUGGAAGGUCCAAAAAUGCUAAUAAGAAAUUAGUAUUUUCACAUAAUACCAAACUGUAAAAACCAGGCCAGCAAGUGUCACCAGGUUCCUGAAACAAACCAUAAAUACAUUAUUUAACUUAGUAUUGUUAAAUUGUAUAAAUAUGUGGGUAACUGUGACAGAAAUUAUGCACUUAUAAAAAGCAGUAAGUUACAUAGUGAAUGCUGUUUUCUGUGGAUAAGAAGCUGGAAUUGUGAUUUCAUUUAAUCGAAAGACGCUUACUUUGAGGAAACUUGUUUGAAAUGCAAACGCGAUUUCUCUGUGGAGCCUUCACGGAAUUGCUGCUUUUCACUAUGAUUAUUGCUGCAUAACAGGCCACUUCUGUGUGUAGGAAGUGCGUGUGCAAGUCCAAAGGGAAUUGAGGCCUGAAUGGGUGGGUUAUCCCAAUUAACAAAUACAAAGUUUUCAGUACAUUUUGUUUUAAGCCAGGUGCACAAGUUAGAGUUGCUUUUUGGGACUGGCAUUUAUGUAUGUGAGAAUCAAACCUGAUAUCACUCUUGGCAGCCUGACUAAAGCCAUUUAAAAAUAAGUACAAAUUGUCCUUGAAUGAUUUUUUUCCCAUUGUAGUAGCACUGAAUUUUCCUUUUUUCUUCAUCUGUGGUACGCAUGCAAUCUUCUGGGUUUUGUUUUUUUGUUUUUUUUUUGAAGAAAUAAGGGAGCUAAGUAUAUACAAAAGACUUUUAGUCUUUUUAUGAAUCAUGUGCUUCAGUGGACUUACUUAUUUUAAAAUUUCUAUGAUACUGUAAUGUGGUACUGUAUGUUGACCUCAAUUCACAUUUAUCCAGAGUAUAAUAGAAACCUCAAUUUUUAAGGAACUUAUAUUAGUAGUUAAGUUUCUUAUGGCCUUGAAAUAAUUUUCUUCAAAUUGGUAUACAAAGAAAUAGUGUAUCCCUGCUAUGUUAAUGACUUUCGUCUAUGUUCUUUUAAGUAAUUUUAUUUUACGAAUUGUGUGUGUGUAUGUGUGUGUGUCUCUGUCUGGUAGCCUACAAUGAAAAUCUGUACAAAUGUGAACAGUUUGUCUCCAGGGGAGAGCCCUGGGGUUUGAUUUCCUGUUUUUGGCUCUGUAAGCUAACGUGUAUGUGCUCCUGGACAGCCCUCUGCUUUGAGAGUAUGAGACCAAGUGUCUUGUGUUCCACAGUAGUAACCUCUUUAGCUAAUGUCGUGUGUGUGUGUGUGUGUGUGUGUGUGUGUGUGUGGGAGGGAGUGUUGAUGGGCUCUGAAAGAAGUCUUGUCUCGUACAUUUCACUGAAUGAAGGCUGCCCAUGACCUAGAGCUUGAUUGUGGGAGGUGAAGAGCAUAUAUGGCUGAAAGACAAUUGCAUAGUGGGGAAAAAAAUUAGGAAAUCCUUACAUUUCUCUUGGUUAGGCAGGAAACAGAGAUGUCCAUAGAAGAAGAGGGAGCUCAUCAGCAUGUUUUAUUAACAGUUAAUGGAAGAAAAUUAAUGCUAAUUUAUUCUUCAUAUACACCAUGCAAUUUGUUAGAAAAGUAAAAGAAUAGUUUGAAAUUCUUUGGUCAAUUGAUGGAUUCCUAUGUUCAGGGCAUAGAAAUGAAACUCAACAUCAAGCAGACAAAUACCCAAGCCCACAGGCUACAUAAAUGCUGAAUAAAACCAGCUCUACAAUGGAACUCUGAAAAGCGACGGGUAAGAAGCCUAAUGAAUGAUUGAAUAUGACCUUAGCAAAAUCCCUGGAGUGUUGUUGAACGAUCAUUCAUUUCCAGCUUAGAUGUCAAGAUGGGCUCCAGUAACCAGGAAAAAAGAGAGCUUGAGUCAGUACUUACUGAGUUUUAAAAAUCUUUUGCAACACAGUGUAUUAGACUGAUCAUUAAAAGGACUUCUCUAGCUGAAUUUUGAGCUGUCACUAUAGUUUAGGCCCAGGGAAAUAAACUUAAAAAGAUAGGAAUAAUUCCUAAGACAUGAAUGUAUCAAUAUCCUAUCCUGCUUUUCUGGAGUAGGACUUCAAAAACUGAAAUGUAUAGGCUGGCAGAAUGUACUUUUGUCAUGCUGAUACCACUGUAAAAGAGACUUAAACUAGGAGAUCAGUUGAGCCCUAAAGUAUUUGCAAAUUACUUGCCUAGCUUGUUAGAAGAAGAAAUAAAAAGCCAAAAUCUA